GAAAUCGGAAAGUUGGCGGGGCUGCGGGAGCUGAGCCUAGAGUCCGGCUGUUGGCUAGAGUGGGCGCGGAUCUGGUGUGGGGAAGGCGGCGGGACUCAGGCCUGCCUGCGAAGCAUUGUCCUACAUAAUGGUAGAGGACGAACUGGCACUUUUCGAUAAAAGCAUAAAUGAAUUUUGGAAUAAAUUCAAAAGUACGGACACCUCCUGUCAGAUGGCGGGACUAAGAGAUACCUACAAGGAUUCCAUCAAAGCAUUUGCAGAAAAGCUGUCUGUGAAAUUAAAGGAAGAAGAACGAAUGGUUGAGAUGUUUCUGGAAUAUCAAAAUCAGAUCAGCAGGCAAAAUAAGCUCAUUCAAGAAAAAAAGGAUAACUUGUUAAAAUUGAUUGCUGAAGUAAAAGGCAAAAAGCAGGAAUUGGAAGUACUGACUGCAAAUAUCCAGGAUCUUAAGGAAGAAUAUUCUAGGAAGAAGGAAACUAUUUCUACUGCUAAUAAAGCGAAUGCAGAGAGGUUGAAAAGGCUGCAGAAAUCUGCAGACUUGUAUAAAGAUCGACUUGGACUAGAAAUUCGAAAAAUUUAUGGUGAGAAAUUGCAGUUUAUUUUCACUAAUAUUGACCCUAAGAAUCCUGAGAGCCCAUUUAUGUUUUCCUUACAUCUCAAUGAAGCAAGGGACUAUGAAGAAAGUCCAGGGAUCCAGAUCCUCCAUGCUGGAUCACAGCAUCCGGGGACCUUUGACAUUCCCCUCAUCCAUCAUCUUCAGCUCUAUCCAGGCUCUGCUUGACCCCCUCAUAGGCCUGCUGUGUUCUGUUGCCACCCAAAUCCAGAGGAAAAAGACAUCUAAGUCCCACUGCUGUUGUCUACCAGAUAACUCUGACUUCAGGCAAGCAGCUGAACCCACCUUGGACUCCGUCUGUUUCUGUGACACCAGGGGUUAUACUGGAUCAUCUCUAGGGUCUCCUAGAAUUUGGAAACUCCUCUAGGAACCAAGGAGCCUCUUCCUUGUCUGUCUCCACCCAUCCAUCUUUUUUCUGACUGUUUCAAGCUAAUAAUCAUGAAUGCAAAGUGCUGUGACAUGCAGGUAGAACUCCAUCCAUUUCAAAAGAAAAACAUGUAAAGGUAAGAGCACUUUAUUCUUAUUUGAACCACACUGUAUUGUUGAUUACCGAGUGUGAAGGUAGUAUGUUCAGAGUCUUGUUUUAUGCCUUUGUAGCUGUGUUGCCAGCAUUUGAAGGUAACUCCUCCACAUAAGCGGCAGGAAAAUGGCCUUUUUUCCCAUUCAAAGAUCCAAACCACCAUCCUUCUUCUUUUUUCUCGUGUAUAAUCACAAUGUCACCUGUGAAAAUACAGUUAGACAAAUGGGUCUCUGUGAUGUGAACACAUGCCUCAGCCCGAUUGAUAAGAGUUUUAAGGAGGUUCUGCUUCAAGGAUUUACUUGGUAGUGUCAUUUUCUGCACUUGAUUCAGAUGAAGCCAAAUGUAUCGAACACCUGUGUAUAAAGCAGGCAUAAUCCAGAGGAUACUAAAAAGAGUAAGAUAAUGAACAACUGAGAUAUAUCAUAAAAUAAUUGCUUAAAGACAGGAUUGGCUGGGCGUGGUGGGUGACGCCUGUAAUCCCAGCACUUUGGGAGGCCAAGGUGUGUGGAUCACAAGGUCAGGAGUUCGAGACCAGCCUGACCAACAUGGUGAAACCCCUUCUCUGCUAAAAAUACAAAAAUUAGCUGGGUGUGGUGGCGCACGCCUGUAAUACCAGCUACUCAGGAGGCUGAGGCAGGAGAAUCCUUGAACCCGGGAGGCAGAGGUUGCAGUGAGCUGAGAUCAUGCCACUGCACUCUAGCCUGGGCAACAGCAACAGGGCAAGACUCUGUCUCAGAAAAAAAAAACAGGAUCACAGCCAGGCACGGUGGCUGACAGCUGUAAUCCCAGCACGUUGGGAGGCCGCGAUGGGCAGAUUAGGCAGAUUACUUGAGGUCAAGAGGUUGAGACCAGCCUGGCCAACAUGGUGAAACCCCGUCUCUACUAAAAAUACAAAAAUUAGCCAGGCAUGGUGGCACACGCCUGUAGUCCCAGCUAUUUGGGAGACUGAGGCAGGAGAAUCACUUGAAUCCAGGAGACGGAGGUUGCAGUGAGCUUGGGAGACUGAGGCAGGAGAAUCACUUGAAUCCAGGAGACGGAGGUUGCAGUGAGCUAAGAUCACACCACUGUACUGCAGCCUGGGUGACAGAGCAAGACUCUGCCUCAAAAAAAAAAAUAAAAAAAGAUCACGUUGGAUCAUAUAUCCUUAUGCUGCCUGGCUCACUUUCUAUUUCUAUGUAGCUGAUGGAUUGUCACCAAACUCUUUCUUGGUGUCUGUACUUUGAGGGUUUCACAUGCUGGUGUUUUUGAUUGUUUGGCGUGUUGGCUGCUAUAAGUAUGUCUCACCAACAGUCUUUUCUUAAGAUCAAGACAAUGUCUCUGCAUUAUACCUGAUUUCACAGGCCAAAAGUUUAACUCACAGCUUUGCACAGAAAUGUAACUCCCCAUUCAAAAUGUAACUCCCCAUUCAACAACUUAGACAACUUUAAUACAACAUCAAUUUGGAGACAAUAUUUUUUAAAGCAAUGAUUCAAAUAAAGAGAAUUCCAUAGAGAAUUGGACAAGAAACAUGGCUCUUGUCAUAAAAGUAGAAAGAUCUGCCCCCUUCAGGAUCAUCUGCCCCCGUCAGGAUCCAAGAGCUACUUUUUCUUUGGCAUCAUUCUGAGGUGAUUUUUCAGUCUUCCUUUCACUCUUUUCCUCAGCAACUUUCUUUCUAAGACAAAGGAGAUUAUUAACUCCUUUUCUAUCUUUUCUACAUUUUCUUAGUCAUAAAUCACUAUUCUUAAAGGACAUCAUUCUCGGUCUCUAAGUUCUCCCUCGUCAGUAAAUUGACAUAAUCUAUUAACAAGAAUUCAAACAAAUAAUGAUUUCAAAUUGUAUUGCCAGCUUCCCUAAGCCUCCAACGUCGUGUUUCAUUUAAAGAAACUGCUUAGAAUAUAAAGUAUAAGUAGGCUUUGCAACCAACAGAGAACUGAAAACAAGAUAAUCAAUUUAUUGUGAAUGAUGUAACUUAAAUGCUGCAUCCAUGGGUUCUAGGUGGCAUCUGGGAAGUAUGUCUUUUAUUCACAUAGGAAGAAAAGUAAUUGCCUGGAGAGAUAUGACUGGCAAAUGCUGCAAAGGAAACACCCAAUAAAUAGCAAAUGUGUGGUGUCCCUGUCGUUUGGCUACAAAAUGUAUCUUGAUUUUCCAUUGGCUCUGGGAGCCAUGUCCUUGUCGUGGAUAAUAUUCUUUCUCCCAUAACGUUACUCUUUCUCACUAACCCUUCCGUUUCCAGAUCUCUGCAUUAGCGCUAACAUUCAAACAUGGUUUCUAACUGGACACAUAAAGAAAUAAAGAAGGUUGAGGCUGGAGACUUUCUUCUUUAAUAAUGUUGUGGUUUACAUUAUAAAGCCACUACGUAAUACCUUUCCAUGUUAAGUAAAACUCUGUGACACAAAGAAGGGGAUCUCACUCUUUAGACUGGCUGUAAAAAGCUUUUCUGAGAAGUAAGUGAGACCAGCACUAAGCUGGGAGUCAGCUGACCUAGGUUCUAGAAUUUGCACUUACUUACACUAAGUUGAGAGAGGAGGUCACUUCACAUUCCUGAAUGUCUAGCUUCUAAAAAAUAAAAAGGUGGGGUACACCUCUAAUCACUUUCCAUCACUGACAUUCUACCCUAGUGUGCACUGUGAUUAGGAGCAUGACUGUGUUUCCAAGUUCAAGUCUUGUGUUGCCACAGCCUGUGACAUUAGCCAAAGCACCUAACCUUCCUGUGUAUCAGUCUCCUCUGCUAUGAAAUGGGAAUACCAAUAAAACCCUCCAAGGGUUUCAUGAAUAUUAAAUUGGACAAUAGGCCUGCAACAAUGUCUGACACACAGUAAACAGAAUAAGCGUUAGCUAUUAUCAUUAUGCGAGCUUUUGUUUUAGAUGUGCUUAUCUUUCAAGAAGGGUGAACUGAUUUGACAUGGUAGUAACUCUUAAGGCUGCCACACUAAGACAGGGUUUUAUUCAUGCUAAGAAUCUCAAUAUGGGAAGGCAAUUAAAAUAUUUGAGAAUGAUUCUUACCCUUUUCCAAAUUCAACUCAUCAUCUUGCCUGGCUUGAAAAGAAUACAAGGCCUUGCAAAGUCUGCUGCUGAGCUGGGCUGCACCAGGGGCUGAAAUAGAUAAAGCUGUAAUUAGUAUGCUGUGUUAGCAGGCAAAUGAAUAUGAGCUGAAGCUCUUUGGUUAUUUAACAGUGUGAUGCAGAGUUUCAAUAUAUUAAAUUUUUCUCAAAAGGAAAGUUUGUAAUUUUAUAUAAUGUUCAUUCCUUGAUUCAAUAACCACUUAUGAUGCACUUUCUAUAUGUAUGGACUGCAUAUGUUAUAUAACCAAAAACUAUAUUAUAAUACAUGAAAUAGCAAGUCUAGAGAAAAACAUCAUUGUAUAAUAAUAGUAAUUGCAUGCAUGUUUUGGAAAACAUUCACCAGUUUUGCCAUUCAGGUAUAAAUACGGGAUAUUUGGGGCAUGUGCAUGUUAUCAUCAUCCCUAGCUGUGUAUGGAACUGUUUCUCAAACAAUGCAACAGUGACUCCUUAAUAUAUUGUGUGAACCAUAA